AGGCGCGGCGCAGGAUGGUGGACAGCGUGUACCGGACCCGCUCCCUGGGGGUGGCGGCCGAAGGGCUCCCGGACCAGUACGCGGACGGGGAGGCGGCGCGCGUGUGGCAGCUGUAUAUCGGAGACACCCGCAGCCGCACCGCCGAGUACAAGGCAUGGCUGCUUGGGCUGCUGCGCCAGCACGGCUGCCAGCGGGUGCUCGACGUAGCCUGUGGCACUGGGGUGGACUCCAUUAUGCUGGUGGAAGAGGGCUUCAGUGUGACGAGUGUGGAUGCCAGUGACAAGAUGCUGAAGUAUGCACUUAAGGAGCGCUGGAACCGGCGGCACGAGCCCGCCUUCGACAAGUGGGUCAUCGAAGAAGCCAACUGGAUGACUCUGGACAAAGAUGUGCCCCAGUCAGCAGAGGGUGGCUUUGAUGCUGUCAUCUGCCUUGGAAACAGUUUCGCUCACUUGCCAGACUGCAAAGGGGACCAGAGUGAGCACCGGCUGGCGCUGAAAAACAUUGCGAGCAUGGUGCGGGCAGGGGGCCUACUGGUCAUUGAUCAUCGCAACUACGACCACAUCCUCAGUACAGGCUGUGCACCCCCAGGGAAGAACAUCUACUAUAAGAGUGACUUGACCAAGGACGUCACAACAUCAGUGCUGAUAGUGAACAACAAGGCCCACAUGGUGACCCUGGACUAUACGGUGCAGGUGCCGGGGGCUGGCCAGGAUGGCUCUCCUGGCUUGAGUAAGUUCCGGCUCUCCUACUACCCACACUGUCUGGCAUCCUUCACGGAGCUGCUCCAAGCAGCCUUCGGAGGUAAGUGCCAGCACAGCGUCCUGGGCGACUUCAAGCCUUACAAGCCAGGCCAAACCUACAUUCCCUGCUACUUCAUCCACGUGCUCAAGAGGACAGACUGAGUGUGGCCUCAGCUCCCACAAGCCUCUGCCCAGGCACUGCUAGGCUCUGUCUGGAAGAUGGGGACCAGCAGCCCCACACCAGGGCCAGCCUCUAGAGCAGACUACAGCUGGGGUGCAGGGAUGUGGGUUCCACAGACGGAAGGGUAAACAAUAUAGUCUUUUUCAGUUCCUGCA